AGCGCUGCUUCCGCGGCGGUUGGGGUGGUGGGGCCCCGGGCGGCGUUGACCAUGACCCAGCAGGGCGCGGCGCUGCAGAACUACAACAACGAGCUGGUCAAGUGCAUAGAGGAGCUGUGCCAGAAGCGGGAGGAGCUGUGCCGGCAGAUCCAGGAGGAGGAGGACGAGAAGCAGCGGCUGCAGAAUGAGGUGAGGCAGCUGACAGAGAAGCUGGCCCGCGUCAACGAGAACCUGGCACGCAAGAUUGCCUCUCGCAACGAGUUCGACCGGACCAUCGCGGAGACGGAGGCCGCCUACCUCAAGAUCCUGGAGAGCUCCCAGACUUUGCUCAGCGUUCUCAAGAGGGAAGCUGGGAACCUGACCAAGGCUACAGCCCCAGACCAGAAAAGUAGCGGCGGCAGGGACAGCUGACCAGACCACGGGCAGGGCCUGCCUCCGUGUGCCCCUCAGCUCAGCCCCAGCAAGUGUGUGCUCAGAGCAUCUUUGUUCUUCACGGCAGCAGCUACCUUCCCUCACUGUCUCAGGUGCCGAGAGGGGCAGGUGCCAGCCUCCACUGGCAUCAGUGACAAGCCCAGGGCACAGCCCACCCGGGGGUCCUCGCUUCAUGCUCACACAGGCUAUGGGGAUGGUGGGCUCCAGGUCAGCUCUGCAAGGGGCUUGUCUCUGUGGCACCCACACUCCUGCCCUGCCAGGGAGGCUCUGGUUGUCUGAGCACCAUGGGGGCCCCCUCACCUUGUCCCUCCUCAGCCAGCAGAGGCCCAGGGCAAGGGACAGGAGGACAGGGGUUCUCCUUCACCACAGAACCCAAACCUCAGGUCUCACCCCUGUGGCCUGUGAUUAUGAAUAAAGAUUAUCUUUGUAAA